AUGAUAUUCUGUUCUCUUGGGACAUUACAGUUUUGCAUAGACAAGGUGAACAUUUCUCAAAACACCAUGUCUCUCCAAUUUUCUAAUGGAUCCAGGCAUGUUUGCUUAAGGUCUGGAGCUGGAUCUGUCAGACCCCUCAAUGGAGGUGCAGGCUUUGCAGGCAGCAGUGCAUGUGGUGGCUCUGUUGCUGGAAGUGAAUUUUCCUGUGCCUUGGGAGGGGGCUUGGGCAGUGUUCCUGGUGGGAGCCAUGCUGGUGGUGCCCUUGGAAAUGCUGCUUGUAUUGGCUUUGCUGGAAGCGAAGGGGGACUCCUCUCUGGAAAUGAGAAGGUGACCAUGCAAAAUCUUAAUGACCGCUUGGCAUCCUACCUGGAUAAUGUGCGAGCUCUGGAGGAGGCAAAUGCUGAAUUAGAGAGAAAAAUCAAGGGUUGGUAUGAAAAAUACGGACCUGGAUCUUGCCGUGGACUUGAUCAUGACUAUAGCAGAUAUCACCUAACAAUUGAGGAUCUUAAGAAUAAGAUUAUCUCCUCCACUACUACUAAUGCUAAUGUCAUUCUGCAGAUUGAUAAUGCCAGACUGGCUGCUGAUGAUUUCAGGCUAAAGUAUGAAAAUGAGCUCACCCUUCACCAAAACGUAGAGGCCGACAUCAACGGAUUACGGCGAGUCCUGGACGAGCUGACGCUCUGCAGGACCGACCAGGAGCUGCAAUAUGAGUCUCUGAGUGAGGAGAUGACAUAUCUCAAAAAGAACCACGAAGAGGAGAUGAAGGCUCUGCAGUGCGCGGCUGGGGGCAACGUGAACGUGGAGAUGAACGCGGCCCCGGGGGUAGACCUCGCGGUUUUGUUGAACAACAUGCGAGCGGAGUACGAAGCCCUUGCAGAGCAGAACCGCAAGGACGCGGAGGCCUGGUUCAAUGAGAAGAGCGCCUCGCUGCAGCAACAGAUCUCCCACGACUCAGGCGCAGCCACUUUCGCCCGGAGCCAGCUCACCGAGAUGAGGCGCACCCUGCAGACCCUGGAGAUCCAGCUGCAGUCCCUGAUGGCCACGAAACACUCCCUGGAGUGCUCCUUGACAGAGACCGAGAGCAACUACUGUACGCAGCUGGCGCAGAUCCAGGCUCAGAUCGGGGCCCUGGAGGAGCAGCUGCACCAGGUCAGAACCGAGACCGAGGGCCAGAAGCUGGAGUAUGAGCAUCUCCUCGAUGUCAAGGUCCACUUGGAAAAAGAAAUUGAGACCUACUGCCGCCUGAUAGAUGGAGAUGGAAAUUCAUGCUCCAAAUCAAAGGGCUUUGGAUCAGGAAGCCCUGGGAAUUCAUCUAAAGAUUUAUCCAAAACCACACUGGUAAAGACAGUGGUUGAAGAGCUAGAUCAACGUGGUAAAGUUCUUUCAUCAAGGAUUCACUCCAUUGAAGAAAAGACAUCUAAAAUGACCAACGGCAAGACAGAACAAAGGGUUCCUUUCUAGCUGUCAUUUUAGAGAAAAGAAUAAUUUGGGAAAGGAUCCUGUACAAUUGCAUUAUUCUAAAUAUCAGAGAGAAUAUACACACUUUUUACUUUUAAAGAUACAUUACUUAGCAAAAAUACCUGUUUUCUUAGUUUUACAGGAUAUUGAGUGUUUGUUUCCAAUAAAUAAAAAAGUUGAUGUGCAUUCAUUUCCAUUCACUGAUGACUAAUAAAUAACUAUUUGUGAUUUUUU